AUGACAGUGCCCUUCAUGUACAGCCCACCGCCAGACACGGGAAAAGUCAUCUCUGACCAGGCAGCCCGCCAGCUGUGUGUUGAGUUUAAGCGUGGCUGUGACAGGUGCGAUCCAAUCUGUCCCGUCCGGGGCCUGGGAAACUCGGCCGCCUAUCCCGCUGCUGCCCACUGCAGAGGCUGCCGGGAAAUACAGGUCCGUGGCCCGGGAGACUCGGCCGCCUAUCCCGCUGCUGCCCACACAGAGGCUGCCGGGAAAUACAGGUCCGUGGCCCGGGAGACUCGGCCACCUACCCCGCUGCUGCCCACUGCAGAGGCUGCCUGGAAAUACAGGUCCGUGGCCCGGGAGACUCGGCCGCCUAUCCCGCUGCUGCCCACACAGAGGCUGCAGGGAAAUACAGGUCCGUGGCCCGGGAGACUCGGCCACCUACCCCGCUGCUGCCCACUGCAGAGGCUGCCUGGAAAUACAGGUCCGUGGCCCGGGAGACUCGGCCGCCUAUGCCGCUGCUGCCCACACAGAGGCUGCCGGGAAAUACAGGUCCGUGGCCCGGGAGACUCGGCCGCCUAUCCCGCUGCUGCCCACGCAGAGGUUGCCGGGAAAUACAGGUCCGUGGCCCGGGAGACUCGGCCGCCUACCCCGCUGCUGCCCACGCAGAGGUUGCCGGGAAAUACAGGUCCCUGGCCCGGGAGACUCGGCCGCCUACCCCGCUGCUGCCCACGCAGAGGCUGCCGGGAAAUACAGGUCCGUGGCCUGGGAGACUCGGCCGCCUACCCCGCUGCUGCCCACGCAGAGGCUGCCGGGAAAUACAGGUCCGUGGCCUGGGAGACUCGGCCGCCUACCCCGCUGCUGCCCACGCAGAGGCUGCCGGGAAAUACAGCAGUCCUCCUGAGCAGCUUCUGACUCUCACCACUUCAUAUCAACUCUCUCGUUCUUGCUUUCCAGGCUCCUGGCUUCAUAUUCUGAAUUUUGCAUCUGCUUCUAAUACUUUUUUUUGAGACCAAGUUUCACUCUGUCACCCAGGCUGGAGUGCAAUGGCACAAUCCCGGCUCACUGCAACCUCCACCGCUUGGGCUCAAGCGAUUCUCAUGCCUCAGCCUCUGAGUAGCUGGAAUUACAGAUGCGCGCCACCACACCCAGUUUAUUUUAUUUUAUUUGUUUUAUUAGUAGACAUGGGGUUUCUCCGUGUUGGCCAGGCUGUCCUCGAACUCCUGACCUCAGGUAAUCCACCCGCCUUGGCCUCCCAAAGUGCUGGGAUUACAGGGUGAGCCACCGUGUCUAGCCUGCUUCUAAUACUUUUAAACUCGUUUGUGGGAUCCAAGCACGUCAAUCCCCCACUUGCUUCUUGUUUCUACCUUCUCUUACUGAAGUGUCUUCUGUGGUUUAAAACAAAAAGGAUUCUCUCCCUGGGGCUCACUCCUGUCACUGACACCACUCUGUCCCUACUCCAUGUCCAGUUAUUCCUGGGGCAUGUGAGAGCUCCUUCCAAAGGCCAUAUCCAACUCUCACGUGAAUUUACCACGUAUCAUCCUUCAAUCCUUGACCUUGGAAAUAAACUUGGAAUUAACUUGGAUCUCA